UGUGAAUAAAGUUCAAUCUUGUCAGACUUAGGACAACUAGGCUGAUCUCGAGCAGGAAGCUGGAUGUUUAUUAAGUCUGAUUUACCUACUCAGUCUGGACUAAAAAGGUGUGUGGAUUCCCUAGUCAGUGACCCAGCAUGAAGCCGGUCACUAGAGUGCCAGGCCCUGAGCCUGUCCCCAUGGCCCUGUGAAGUACAAAGCGCUGCCCUACCUCUCAAGUGAGCACGCUGAGGCUCCAGGAGCUUCAUCAUCCCCGAGUCACCGGCCAGGUCGGGCCAUCUAGGGAAACUGGAGAGUGUUAACUCCGCAGUUACAGCCUUCUGGGCCACACACUGUCCCAAAGCUGGAAUUUGAGCUCUGUUCUGCCUGGCUCCAAAGCAAAAGAAGGGCAAUCACCUGGGCUGACCGCCCACGACAUCCUUCGCUCCGGGUCCUUUCCCGGUGGCAGGUGGAGACGGCCUUUUGGAGGGGCCUCGCUGUCCAGCUGCAAGGAUAGUGGUUAGUGGACAGCUCCCAGCUGCUGGCCCCUGCAGGGUGGGCCUUGCUUUUAUGCUGAGCUCAUGCUCUUCUCCAGGUGACCCUGUGGCCGAUGACUAAGCAAAGUGGCAUCACAGUGACCUCACCAUUUCCACCCCACAAGACUCCGCCAACAGGCAGUCUGCCCCUCAGAGCGCCCCAUGGGCAGGAGCUUUGUGGCUGUGUCAGCUGUGCCACAUCCUCCUGCCCAGCCCGGCCUCCUUCUUCUUACACAGGUGCCACAUCCUCCUGCCCAGCCCGGCCUCCUUCUCCUUACGCAGGUGCCACAUCCUCCUGCCCAGCCCGGCCUCCUUCUCCUUACGCAGGUGCCACAUCCUCCUGCCCAGCCCGGCCUCCUUCUCCUUACGCAGGUGCCACAUCCUCCUGCCCAGCCCGGCCUCCUUCUCCUUACGCAGGUGCCACAUCCUCCUGCCCAGCCCGGCCUCCUUCUCCCUACGCAGGUGCCACAUCCUCCUGCCCAGCCCGGCCUCCUUCUCCUUACGCAGGUGCCACAUCCUCCUGCCCAGCCCGGCCUCCUUCUCCUUACGCAGGUGCCACAUCCUCCUGCCCAGCCCGGCCUCCUUCUCCUUACGCAGGUGCCACAUCCUCCUGCCCAGCCCGGCCUCCUUCUCCUUACGCAGGUGCCACAUCCUCCUGCCCAGCCCGGCCUCCUUCUCCUUACGCAGGUGCCACAUCCUCCUGCCCAGCCCGGCCUCCUUCUCCUUACACAGGUGCCACAUCCUCCUGCCCAGCCCGGCCUCCUUUUCCUUACACAGGUGCCACAUCCUCCUGCUCAGCCCGGCCUCCGCCCUUCUCCUUACGCAGAUGCCACAUCCUCCUGCCCGGCCCGGCCUCCUUCUCCUUACCAGGUGCCACAUCCUCCGCCCAGCCUGGCCUCCGCCCUUCUCCUUACCAGGUGCCACAUCCUCCUGCUCAGCCUGGCCUCCGCCCUUCUCCUUACAAGGUGCCACAUCCUCCUGCUCAGCCUGGCCUCCGCCGUUCUCCUUACCAGGUGCCACAUCCUCCUGCCCAGCCUGGCCUCCGCCCUUCUCCUUACGAGGUGCCACAUCCUCCUGCCCAGCCUGGCCUCCGCCCUUCUCCUUACGAGGUGCCACAUCCUCCUGCCCAGCCUGGCCUCCGCCCUUCUCCUUACCAGGUGCCACAUCCUCCUGCUCAGCCUGGCCUCCGCCCUUCUCCUUACCAGGUGCCACAUCCUCCUGCCCGGCCCGGCCUCCUUCUCCUUACGCAGGUGCCACAUCCUCCUGCCCGGCCUCCUUCUCCUUACCAGGUGCCACAUCCUCCUGCCCAGCCCGGCCUCCUUCUCCUUACCAGGUGCCACAUCCUCCUGCCCAGCCCGGCCUCCUUCUCCUUACGCAGGUGCCACAUCCUCCUGCCCGGCCCGGCCUCCUUCUCCUUACACAGAUGCCACAUCCUCCUGCCCGGCCCGGCCUCCUUCUCCUUACCAGGUGCCACAUCCUUCUGCCCGGCCCGGCCUCCUUCUCCUUACCGGGUGCCACAUCCUCCUGCCCGGCCUCCUUCUCCUUACCAGGUGCCACAUCCUCCUGCCCGGCCCGGCCUCCUUCUCCUUAUGCAGGUGCCACAUCCUCCUGCCCGGCCUCCUUCUCCUUACCAGGUACCACAUCCUCCUGCCCAGCCCGGCCUCCUUCUCCUUACCAGGUGCCACAUCCUCCUGCCCAGCCCGGCCUCCUUCUCCUUACGCAGGUGCCACAUCCUCCUGCCCGGCCUGGCCUCCUUCUCCUUACACAGAUGCCACUUCCUCCUGCCCGGCCCGGCCUCCUUCUCCUUACAAGGUGCCACAUCCUCCUGCCCAGCCCGGCCUCCUUCUCCUUACCAGGUGCCACAUCCUCCUGCCCGGCCCAGCCUCCUUCUUCUUACCAGGUGCCACAUCCUCCUGCCCGGCCCGGCCUCGUUCUCCUUACACAGGUGCCACAUCCUCCUGCCCGGCCCGGCCUCCUUCUCCUUACCAGCAUUUGCUUCUGGGAGGACCCGACCCGAGACACUCACGUAAAAGAGGAUGCCCACGUACAGAUGUGGCAGCAGGCCCUCCGAGCUGGGAUUCAGACCCAGCCUUAAGGAGAAGAAAACCGAGGCCAGGAAGUCAGCAAGAACAUGAAGUCGGUGACCCAGCAUCCAGGUCCCCGGAUUUGCCACCUGUGUCCUUUUGUGGGGCUUCCCUUUGUAAAGCUUGAAAGAAUAAGAGGAUCUUAACAUAAUUUUAAAACUGGAAGAGACCCUGGUGACCAUGUCAUCCGAAGCCCUCAUUCUACCGUGGAGGAGGUGUGGGCCCAGAGAGAAGGGAGGUCCUUGUUGGCGCAGCCGGUGAGCGGCAGGGUGUGUCCCGGAGCCCGGGUUUCCAGCGCCCUCUCUGUCUUGCUGCCGAGCGUCCACGUCUGUUCGGUUGUCUUUGCACACUCCUGGCUCCCAGUUAGACCGCUGCUCCCAGGCGGAACGUCUGCCACAGGGGACACGUACAUGCGGCCACCAUGGGGACUGAAUGAGGGUGGGCCCACAAAGCUCUCCAACGCGGGGUUCUGACAGAAAGCCCAACCCGGGCCGAAAGCCAUCUUUUAAAAUGAAGUUUACUGGGUUUCUUUUUUCAUUAUAAAGUAAUGCACACUGUCCACAGAGAUAUGAAAAUAUUUAAAAGUAGAGAGAAGAAAAACAUCA